UGUUUGUUUUAUUCUCAGUCUUUGAGGUUUUUUCAAAUACCUAUUUACCCUAAAUUAGUGGCUCAUGUGUAUGAGAAUGGAUCACAGAAGAACUGACUGGAAGCUCUGUUGUCACCAGUGGGCCUCAUGUAGGAUAACAUUGCAGAGCUGUUUCACUGAGAAACUCACAAGAUUACUAUCUUUAUGCUCUUUAUUCUUGACCUGGUCAAAUUACCCAGUAAAGAAGGCGCGUACCAGGCUGCAUUGAGUUCUGGAAGCCAUGUGGGGAAGGUGAACUGGAGGAGGCAACAUCCAGUGUGAAUGUUCACUGAAUGUUUGCAGUAAGAUGGUACUCCUGCCCUCUUCUGUGCUUGGUGUCCUACAGUCCUUGGCCUUGAUGGUAAAAUAGAAAAGUAAAGAAGGCAUCUCAGUGAUAUGUGUGUUGCUUUUACCCUUCUAAUCUCCUGCAGGGGUAGGAAAGAAUACUGCUAGCGUGUAGGGAAUAGGAAAGGAUAUCUGAAGUUCUAAUUACUGUAUGUAUAUUUUCAGCCUCAUGCUAUUUUAAUAUCCCCUUCCCCCUUUUAGAAGUACUUUUAGAAGUACCUUUGAUACCGUUUCUGGAGCCUUUUUGGUGUUAAGCAGUAAAGCUUUGCUUCUUAGCUUUCCCCCCACAUUUGGCUUAAAAAUCAGCUUUUGUAGCUUUAUUAUCAAUUCAAUAUAUCAGAAUUUACUCUCUAAUUAUUAACUCUAAUAUUUCAUUAGAUUAUUCAAAAUUUAUACAAGAUGUGCAUCUAACUUUCUCCUACAGUUUCCUGUAAAUUUUGUCCAGAAAAAAAAAUGUUGAUUGCAGUGGGCACCUGUGGCAUAUGAGAAGAUUGUCAUAUGCAGAAUCCGACCUUGAGCCACAGCAAUUUUGAUCCUGUAGACAAGUGACUGCCUGUCUUUCUGCUUUUCAGGCUUUUAUUUUAGUGUCUCCUCCCUUGAUCUCAUAUUGUAGGCUCAUUUUCUUAGCCCCUUUUUCUCUUAUUAUAGUGGGAUUUAAUAACUAGAAUACCCUGUAAGUAAAACCAAAAAUUAUACUAUAACAUUUUUUCUUGUCAGUAAAUAUACUUCUGCAUCAGCAUUUUAAUGGCUAUAUAGGAAUCCCAUUUUACAAAUAUACCUAAUCCUCUAGUGUUGUAAAUAUGAGUUGUUAUAAGCAAUAUUGUGAAGAACCAAAUUUUAUACCACUUCUUCUAGACAAAUUUUAUACCACUCUUUAAAUAAAUUCACAAUGUGACAAAAUCAUGAAUUGUCUCUUAAAAUGUUUCUUAGAAAAUAGCAUCUUACUUCCAAUCACAUGAGGAUAUUUUCUUUUCUACUUUAGACCAUUUGGUGUCAGUGUUCCAUUUAACAGCUUUUCCCACCAGCUGGUAAAUUCUGUGUGUGUUUAAUUCAUCCUAGUUAAACAGGCUGUGCCUGGAAAAUGGGAGGGCACCCAAUACAUAUUUGGUAGUAGACAUUUGCAUCAUAAAUGAAUUUUUAUUAUUGUGUUUUAAAGCAUCAAAAAUAAAGGGUCUGGUAUGAAAGGAAGCAGGAAGUAAUAAAUUUUAAAUACUCUAUUUUUAUUACUUGGUCUACUGAGGUGACUCAGGUCAUAAAGGCAGUAACAUUGAGAACCAGGUUUAGAAAGAAGGAGCUUACCAUGACAGGGUGAGAUAUAGGUACACCUACACACUCUACCCUGGCAUAGCAAGCGGUGCUGCACUCCCAUGUGGACAAACUUGGAACAAAUGGCUUUCAAGAUAAGGCAGUGACGUGAACUAUUUAACCUCACUUUAUUUGGGAAUUUAACCUAAGGACGAGCAUACUAUAUAGAAAUAAUACAUGUAUUGGGAGUAAUUGUGUGGUUGGAUUACAUAUUAUUUGCUUAAUCUAGGGUUUUUCUAAGUGGAGUCUACAAGUAAUUUGUUUCAGAAUUACAUGAGAUCUUGUUGAAUAUGCACAUUUCCUGGCUCGCCUCUGACCUACAGAAUCAAAAUCACUGUGGCUGGGGUGGGAUUCUGCAUACGACAAUCUUCUCAUAUGCCACAGGUGCCCACUGCAAUCAACAUUUUUUUUUUCUGGACAAAAUUUACAGGAAACUGUUUGAGAAAGUUAGAUGCACAUCUUUUAUAAAUUUGAAUAAUCUAAUGAAAUAUUAUAGUUAAUAGAGAGAAAAUUCUGAUAUAUUGACAACAUAUUUUAUUGCUUUUUCUUUCAACUAUUUUUUUCUGUAAGAAUUUGAAUAAUUCGUUAUACAUGCAGAAGGUCAGGAAAAAUUAUCACAGAUUAAAAAAAAUAGACUUCUAAUUCUCUGAUGGAACCAUUACCUGCAGGCCUUCAUUUUUGGUUUAAAAAUAUAACAAAUAUGUGGCAUAUCUUAUACUUCUGACCUAAAAUUUCAAUUUUUUAACCCAGCAAUUUUUUAAUAUUUUUGUUGAUCUUAGAUUUCACUAUAGAUAAGCUAAAUGUGUUAUGAGAGAGAUUUUAAAUUGAAAACUGCUCACGGUGACAAUUUAUGCAGUUACAUGGCAUGUAUAAGAGCUCUUACCACAACGCCUGAAACAAAAUAGCAAACUUCCUUGAUAACAUGCUUUUGCGAAGUGCAGGAAAAUUAAAUGUGGGCACCAAGAAAGAGGAUGGUGAGAGUACAGCCCCCACCCCCCGUCCAAAGGUCUUGCGUUGUAAAUGCCACCACCAUUGUCCAGAAGACUCAGUCAACAAUAUUUGCAGCACAGACGGAUAUUGUUUCACGAUGAUAGAAGAGGAUGACUCUGGGUUGCCUGUGGUCACUUCUGGUUGCCUAGGACUAGAAGGCUCAGAUUUUCAGUGUCGGGACACUCCCAUUCCUCAUCAAAGAAGAUCAAUUGAAUGCUGCACAGAAAGGAACGAAUGUAAUAAAGACCUACACCCUACACUGCCUCCAUUGAAAAACAGAGAUUUUGUUGAUGGACCUAUACACCACAGGGCUUUACUUAUAUCUGUGACUGUCUGUAGUUUGCUCUUGGUCCUUAUCAUAUUAUUUUGUUACUUCCGGUAUAAAAGACAAGAAACCAGACCUCGAUACAGCAUUGGGUUAGAACAGGAUGAAACUUACAUUCCUCCUGGAGAAUCCCUGAGAGACUUAAUUGAGCAGUCUCAGAGCUCAGGAAGUGGAUCAGGCCUCCCUCUGCUGGUCCAAAGGACUAUAGCUAAGCAGAUUCAGAUGGUGAAACAGAUUGGAAAAGGUCGCUAUGGGGAAGUUUGGAUGGGAAAGUGGCGUGGCGAAAAGGUAGCUGUGAAAGUGUUCUUCACCACAGAGGAAGCCAGCUGGUUCAGAGAGACAGAAAUAUAUCAGACAGUGUUGAUGAGGCAUGAAAACAUUUUGGGUUUCAUUGCUGCAGAUAUCAAAGGGACAGGGUCCUGGACCCAGUUGUACCUAAUCACAGACUAUCAUGAAAAUGGUUCCCUUUAUGAUUAUCUGAAGUCCACCACCCUAGACGCUAAAUCAAUGCUGAAGUUAGCCUACUCUUCUGUCAGUGGCUUAUGUCAUUUACACACAGAAAUCUUUAGUACUCAAGGCAAACCAGCAAUUGCCCAUCGAGAUCUGAAAAGUAAAAACAUUCUGGUGAAGAAAAAUGGAACUUGCUGUAUUGCUGACCUGGGCCUGGCUGUUAAAUUUAUUAGUGAUACAAAUGAAGUUGACAUACCACCUAACACUCGAGUUGGCACCAAACGCUAUAUGCCUCCAGAAGUGUUGGACGAGAGCUUGAACAGAAAUCACUUCCAGUCUUACAUCAUGGCUGACAUGUAUAGUUUUGGCCUCAUCCUUUGGGAGGUUGCUAGGAGAUGUGUAUCAGGAGGUAUAGUGGAAGAAUACCAGCUUCCUUAUCAUGACCUAGUGCCCAGUGACCCCUCUUAUGAGGACAUGAGGGAGAUUGUGUGCAUCAAGAAGUUACGCCCCUCAUUCCCAAACCGGUGGAGCAGUGAUGAGUGUCUAAGGCAGAUGGGAAAACUCAUGACAGAAUGCUGGGCUCACAAUCCUGCAUCAAGGCUGACAGCCCUGCGGGUUAAGAAAACACUUGCCAAAAUGUCAGAGUCCCAGGACAUUAAACUCUGAUAGGAGAGGAAAAGUAAGCAUCUCUGCAGAAAGCCAACAGGUACUCUUCUGUUUGUGGGCAGAGCAAAAGACAUCAAAUAAGCAUCCACAGUACAAGCCUUGAACAUCGUCCUGCUUCCCAGUGGGUUCAGACCUCACCUCUCAGGGAGCGACCUGGGCAAAGACAGAGAAGCUCCCAGAAGGAGAGAUUGAUCCAUGUCUGUUUGUAGGACGGAGAAACCGCUUGGGUAACUUGUUCAAGAUAUGAUGCAUGUUGCUUUCUAAGAAAGCCCUGUAUUUUGUGAUUGCCUUUUUUUUUUUUUAAGAUGCUUUCAUUUUGCCAAAAUAAAACAGAUAAUGUGGAUGGUUUAAGGGUUAUAGUAUUAUAGUUUAAAUAAUAACAACAAAAUUCUUCCCAGGAACUCUGCUGGAAGGUAAAUUAAAAUACUUGUUUUUCCAUUGGUAAAAUAUUGUUGCACUCUGUGAACCAAAAGACAGUCUAAGUUGGAGGACAUAGAACGGAACUCAUCUUAAACAUACUCCCCACCCCGUCUUGGCCUCCUCAGACCACUUUGGCCAUCCCUGCAUUUGGGGCCGCUAUGGUAAUGUGAAUGCACUGGGUACAAACACCGCCUGUCUAGGACCACAUUUGGAAUUCCUGCAGGUGGCCUUUUGCAGCUUCAGGCAAUAUGGAACAAAUGAAGGUUUAUGUGACUCUAAUAGAAGUAAUUGUUGAUAGGUGUUCUUCAGAUCCACUUCUGUUUCUGAUUGAGUUAGGCAUCUCUUUCAUGGUAAAACCCUUUUCAUUAAACACAAAGAAAGCUUUUUUUUUUUUUUUUUUUUUUUUUUUUUUUUAAUGUGCAGAGGAUUGACCUGUGCAUGCUUUUGAUCUCUCAUUCAAAGGAUCAAUAUUAAAUAAAAUUGUCAUGAGCUGUGUUGAAGACAGGGUGCUUUCAAAUAGAGGUAAUUUGCUCUUGUGUUGUAAGAGGAACAUGUCAACAAAGAUAGGAAAUGAGGGUGAUCGUGCAGAUGGCUUGUAUCUUAUAUAUGCAAAGGAGCCAAUCUCAGAAGCACAAAGAAAAAAGUGUGCAUACCUUAUUUUGUACAGAUAAAGAUGAUGUCUUUUUGUUAUUGUCUGUCUGUUUUGUAUGUGUCUGAGAUAAGGGAUAGAGAGGAAACAUCCGUCAGGCUAAUUUAACUACAUUUUAUUUUAAAAAUAGAGAAACAUAACCUCUAGAUGGGACAGCAGAGGACAGUUAGUAGAGGCCACAAACUGUUAUGGGCUGCUGUGUUUUGUUCUAAAAUCAAUAUGGUUGGAGCAUGUAUAUCUUAGGUGAUCAUUUCACAUCUUAGGAAUGCCUACUCAUUUUAUUUUAUUCUAGUGAUGCUCAAUUCACUAUUUAAUUUAUUAUAUUUUCUCUUCUGUGGCACUUAUACAAAAUAUCUCUUCACCUACUUAGUUCUACAGGGUUUUAACUUUGGAGCAACAUGAAUAAAAUCAUCGAGAAGGCCAAUAUUGUUUAGCAACAUGAAUACAAUACAGUUUAAAGUUGUACACAUCCUGCUCAACUUUAUUCAUAUACAUUUCCUUUCUGUGGUUUUCUUUUGCUUCUUAGAAAUUCUGUUAGUGGUUAGUAAAGAAUUUGAAAGUACUUUCUCCUUGCUGUUUUUUUUUUUUUUUAAGACAUUCCUCCCAGAAUACUCCAGGGGGCAGUGUUUUAUAACACAUUUUCCCCACUGGGUGAUUGAAGGAUGGAGGAUUUUUGAAAAUUUGACAGCUACAUGAAACAUGAGAAAACAUUUUCCUCACUUCUGAAGUCGGUUUGCAGCUGGUAACUUGUUCAUCCAGAAAACAUUCUAAAGCAAUGAGACUUUGUGAGCUGUGCUUACAGUUUGGGAGAAUCAUGAAGAUUCUUUCUAUAUUUUGCAUUUACUUCCCAGUGCUUCAUAGCUGCAUUUUGUUUGUAACUAAGACAGAAGAAUUUCGUAAUCCUUGAAAUUGAAAAAAAAAAAAUUGUGUUUUUAAAGAGUGAAAACAGUUAGAAAACAAGUAGAACUGUAAUCAGAACGCUGCUUCAAUUGAUAUUAAAAAUAACCUCAAUAAUAAUGUAAAGGUUCCUUUCUCUUGUGUCAGUUAUAUUCUUAGGGAUAGCCUAGAAGGAAUAUAUGGUUAGAACUAAGUGUGACUAAUCAUCUGAGCCUUGAAGAGAAACUUCAGUGCCUCUAAACAGAUCAUCUACAAAACAACAGGUAAACAUUUAUGCCAGUUAAGUGGGUCAUGUUUUUGUUUCUUGGGUUUUUCCUAAAUUUAAGUGAGGUUGGGCUUACCUUGUAGAUAAAAUUAUGUUUUCUUUUUGGUAAAUACUUGAACGUGGAUAACGUCAAAUCAGAAUAUUUUGUGAGGAGGUGAUGAUUUGAAAUUAAGCUAGAUUUCUAGGGAGGUGUUGGUUCCAAUGAAGGAUGGGAAGAAAUUAAAAUAGUCUUCAAACUUCUUCCUUAUUAUAUUUGGUUGCUUUGGAAAAGAUUGGUCCUAUCCUCAAUCUAAUUUAUUCACUAUUAAUAUUUUAAAAACAUUCCUGAGAUACUUAAAAAGACCCACUUAGCGAUUAUAGUUGCUCAAUGAAACAAGAAUUUAUUUAUGCAUAGAUUUUUCUCUGUAUCUUACCAAAAUCCACUUUACUUAGAUAACACUAAAUUGUUCUUAAAGACUACUCAUUUCCCAAUAAUCCUUUAUGAUUUCAAAAUUUCUAGUGGCUCAGAAGUGAAUUUUAUUUUAUUUGUCUUUCACUUGAAUAAAUGAGAACCCAGAAAUUAAUAAUGUUGUUUAUUGCUUACUGUCAGGACUAUUUCAAAGACUAAGAAGAGUUUCUUCUAACCCCUCCCUCUCAAAGGAAUCCUAAAUUAUUAGUUGUUAGAUAAGUUUUGUAUGCUAAGAUAUUCAGGUUUAUAGUUUAUGUAUGUGUGUAUAUAUAUAAAUAUAUAUGUAUAUAUAAAUAUUAUGUUCAGUUUGGAGUCUGGCACAACUCCAUUAUGUGGAUUAGAGAGUAAGAUAUUAUGGAUGAUAAAGUACUAAAUGAAACAUAAUAUUUAUUUAUAAAAGUGUGUAGAUUGUUAAAUCACAAAAAGAGUGCUAUGACCAUUAUGUAUGAGGAAACAGGCCUUUGACCUCCUGGAAAGCACUGCUCAAAAGUCAUUAGUGCCCAUUUUUGAAUUCCCCAAACAGAAAGCUUCUUAGAAAACAUGCUGAGAUUUUAUUUACAGGGAAUUCUUUGACACAUUUCAAUUGGUGUGUAGUCAAGUAUAGCAAGUACUUAAUAAUGACUGAAUUUCAUGUUCCUACAGUCAUACAUAUUCAUUAGAAGUUUUAUGUUGUUGGUCUGAUCUGAUUCUUCUUUGUUUGUGGGUGGAACGGCACUGAGAGAAGUAUAGUUUUUUAAACUUGAACAUGUUCAGUAGUUACAUUGCCUUAGAAAACCCAGACACAUAGCAGUGGAAAUGAAAGAAAUGGCAUCAGAAGUGACUUAAUUUAGCAAUUGUGAUUCCUCUUGUAAAACAAAACAAAAAAACAAUGCCAUAUUUUUUGGAGAAAAGUUGGCAAUAUAGGGGUUUCGUUGUCUGUUUCACAAGAAGACUCAUUUGUUCUUUUGGGGGAACCAGUGCCUUACAGAUUUUGUAUAUACUGUAAUUAUUCAGGACUAGGGAACAAACAAUUGUAUUGUAUUUGUUACAGAUUGUAUAUGGCUUUGUUUUAACAUUCCCCUAAAUAAAAUGGCUUCAUUCUCCCCUUGGAAAAAAACA